AGAGGCGGGUCAGAGCAGGCAGGGGGUUCGUGACGCCGGCUGGGUCUGGGGGCUGUGGGCCAGCCGAGCCGACCCGGGCUUCUGGGGGACCGCGGGGGCCGUGAGCACUCAGAGGGCGCAUCCCAGGCCCCUCCGGGGACCCGGCCAGCCUGAAGAUGCCGACGAACGGCCUGCACCAGGUGCUGAAGAUCCAGUUUGGCCUCGUCAACGACACUGACCGCUACCUGACAGCUGAGAGCUUCGGCUUCAAGGUCAAUGCCUCGGCACCCAGCCUCAAGAGGAAGCAGACCUGGGUGCUGGAACCCGACCCAGGACAAGGCACGGCUGUGCUGCUCCGCAGCAGCCACCUGGGCCGCUACCUGUCGGCAGAAGAGGACGGGCGCGUGGCCUGUGAGGCAGAGCAGCCGGGCCGUGACUGCCGCUUCCUGGUCCUGCCGCAGCCAGAUGGGCGCUGGGUGCUGCGGUCCGAGCCGCACGGCCGCUUCUUCGGAGGCACCGAGGACCAGCUGUCCUGCUUCGCCACAGCCGUUUCCCCGGCCGAGCUGUGGACCGUGCACCUGGCCAUCCACCCGCAGGCCCACCUGCUGAGCGUGAGCCGGCGGCGCUACGUGCACCUGUGCCCGCGGGAGGACGAGAUGGCCGCAGACGGAGACAAGCCCUGGGGCGUGGACGCCCUCCUCACCCUCAUCUUCCGGAGCCGACGGUACUGCCUCAAGUCCUGUGACAGCCGCUACCUGCGCAGCGACGGCCGUCUGGUCUGGGAGCCUGAGCCCCGUGCCUGCUACACGCUGGAGUUCAAGGCGGGCAAGCUGGCCUUCAAGGACUGCGACGGCCACUACCUGGCACCCGUGGGGCCCGCAGGCACCCUCAAGGCCGGCCGAAACACGCGACCUGGCAAGGAUGAGCUCUUUGAUCUGGAGGAGAGUCACCCACAGGUGGUGCUGGUGGCUGCCAACCACCGCUACGUCUCUGUGCGGCAAGG